CUCGGGCCAAUAACUGCGCAGCGCGCGGGACCCGGGUGGGGAAGCUGGAGCUGUUGCGGGGUCCGCGGGGAAGUCUUGGCGGUGGAGCCAUGGUCGGCCAACUGAGCGAGGGGGCCAUUGCGGUGAGGAGGCCAUCAUGCAGAAGGGGGAUACAAACAUAAAGCCCAUCCUCCAAGUCAUCAACAUCCGUCCCAUUACUACGGGGAAUAGUCCGCCGCGUUAUCGACUGCUCAUGAGUGAUGGAUUGAACACUCUAUCCUCUUUCAUGUUGGCGACACAGUUGAACCCUCUCGUGGAGGAAGAACAAUUGUCCAGCAACUGUGUAUGCCAGAUUCACAGAUUUAUUGUGAACACUCUGAAAGACGGAAGGAGAGUAGUUAUCUUGAUGGAAUUAGAAGUUUUGAAGUCAGCUGAAGCAGUUGGAGUGAAGAUUGGCAAUCCAGUGCCCUAUAAUGAAGGACUCGGGCAGCCGCAAGUAGCUCCUCCAGCGCCAGCAGCCAGCCCAGCAGCAAGCAGCAGGCCCCAGCCGCAGAAUGGAAGCUCGGGAAUGGGUUCUACUGUUUCUAAGGCUUAUGGUGCUUCAAAGACAUUUGGAAAAGCUGCAGGUCCCAGCCUGUCACACACUUCUGGGGGAACACAGUCCAAAGUGGUGCCCAUUGCCAGCCUCACUCCUUACCAGUCCAAGUGGACCAUUUGUGCUCGUGUUACCAACAAAAGUCAGAUCCGUACCUGGAGCAACUCCCGAGGGGAAGGGAAGCUUUUCUCCCUAGAACUGGUUGACGAAAGUGGUGAAAUCCGAGCUACAGCUUUCAAUGAGCAAGUGGACAAGUUCUUUCCUCUUAUUGAAGUGAACAAGGUGUAUUAUUUCUCGAAAGGCACCCUGAAGAUUGCUAACAAGCAGUUCACAGCUGUUAAAAAUGACUACGAGAUGACCUUCAAUAACGAGACUUCCGUCAUGCCCUGUGAGGACGACCAUCAUUUACCUACGGUUCAGUUUGAUUUCACGGGGAUUGAUGACCUCGAGAACAAGUCGAAAGACUCACUUGUAGACAUCAUCGGGAUCUGCAAGAGCUAUGAAGACGCCACUAAAAUCACAGUGAGGUCUAACAACAGAGAAGUUGCCAAGAGGAAUAUCUACUUGAUGGACACAUCCGGGAAGGUGGUGACUGCUACACUGUGGGGGGAAGAUGCUGAUAAAUUUGAUGGUUCUAGACAGCCCGUGUUGGCUAUCAAAGGAGCCCGAGUCUCUGAUUUCGGUGGACGGAGCCUCUCCGUGCUGUCUUCAAGCACUAUCAUUGCGAAUCCUGACAUCCCAGAGGCCUAUAAGCUUCGUGGAUGGUUUGACGCAGAAGGACAAGCCUUAGAUGGUGUUUCCAUCUCUGAUCUAAAGAGCGGCGGAGUCGGAGGGAGUAACACCAACUGGAAAACCUUGUAUGAGGUCAAAUCCGAGAACCUGGGCCAAGGCGACAAGCCGGACUACUUUAGUUCUGUGGCCACAGUGGUGUAUCUUCGCAAAGAGAACUGCAUGUACCAAGCCUGCCCGACUCAGGACUGCAAUAAGAAAGUGAUUGAUCAACAGAAUGGAUUGUACCGCUGUGAGAAGUGCGACACCGAAUUUCCCAAUUUCAAGUACCGCAUGAUCCUGUCAGUAAAUAUUGCAGAUUUUCAAGAGAAUCAGUGGGUGACUUGUUUCCAGGAGUCUGCUGAAGCUAUCCUUGGACAAAAUGCUGCUUAUCUUGGGGAAUUAAAAGACAAGAAUGAACAGGCAUUUGAAGAAGUUUUCCAGAAUGCCAACUUCCGAUCUUUCAUAUUCAGAGUCAGGGUCAAAGUGGAGACCUACAACGACGAGUCUCGAAUUAAGGCCACUGUGAUGGACGUGAAGCCCGUGGACUACAGAGAGUAUGGCCGAAGGCUGGUCAUGAGCAUCAGGAGAAGUGCAUUGAUGUGAGAGGAGCAGUGCCAAUCGGGCAGAAGUUUGCAAAUAGGCAGAAUGGAAUCGAUUUCCUCCCACCUCCGUGUGACGAUCCCAUGUUAGCUACACAGUGCAGAGGCUCUUGAUGGUGGACUAAGCAAUUUCCCCCCUCGUGCGCAUCUCAGAACCCAUCGGUAGGCAAAGGAAAAUACGCUCAGGUGGUUGUGGUGUAGACUGUGUCAGGCCUACGGAGUCAGCCAGUGGCUAGCGCAAGACCAGUCACUCCCUCUGCCUUCAGGCUUCUGUCAAUUUCAUUAUCAUCAAGCAGGAAUUAUGUCGUAAGUCACUGACCCUAACUGCAGACCAUGAAGUAAAUUAUGUAACUAGGUUUUUGCUUCUCCAGUGGUGACCACCCCCCCCCAUCCCCGCUCACAACUUGGGUUCUUCUCAGCGGGGCGAGCUGAGAAGCGGUCAUGAGCACCUGGGGAUUUUAGUAAGUGUGUCUUCCUAGAAUUCGAAGGCUCUCUCUUUCUAGAGGUGCUACAUAGUUGGUAAUGCUUGGAAUGGCAAUAGGGUAGAAUGAUUAAUCAAAGGCAUAUCUUCUAUAUCUGAAGAGUAUCCUUCCUUCAGGGUUUAAUAGACUGAGUCAGAUGGGUCUGAUAUUAAUCAAAAUUGUCUCUUCUGAGGACCGCUGAUAAGCAUUGACUUGCCGUCCCCUAAGGAAAUCCGAGCGGCUACAAAGCGUUUCUUUACUUCUCACUUCAAUUAAUGCUGCGCUUCGCUUGGUGAGUGCGUACUUUUUCUACCUGUACACAUUCCUGCAUUCAUGUAUUUUGUUUUUUUUGACUAAAGCUAUGUUACAUGGAAAGGAUUUUGAAGCCUUUUGUUUCCCUUGCUUUGUUUUAAUAAACAGUAUAUUCUUUGGUUGUGAAUCCUACUUUCUUUGAAUGCAAAGAGUUCCUAUAACUGGAAAGCAAUUAAUUAGCCUUCAUAAUAAAUGUUCACUUGGGGGGGAUGUUAACUCAUUAUAAACCCGAAGAUUAGUCCAAGGCAUGGAGAUCCUUCUUCCUAGUGUUUGCAGCCCUGAAAUGCAUCUUUCAAAGCAUGAAAACACUAAAAACAAAAAGCCAUUUUGCCUGAGGAUGCUGAUGAUCUGGCACUUGGGAUUUUAUUGAUGUUUACGCAGCAGUCUAACACCAACCACGCUUUGAAAUGUGUACAGACAGUGAGCUGGUAAGAAAACAGUAAUUAUGCUAGUGGGCCUUUCAGUCAGCAAAAGCAUGCUCGCUCUGUGUGUUCCUAAUCAUAUUAAUUAUCUAUCCGGUGGCUGCAACACACCGCCUGCCAUUGGCCGCACAUCUCGCCGUCGUACCCCGGCAGUGCGGCGGUCACUCUGCAGCCAGAGGACCUGCUGUUCAUCACUGCACAUGCCGCCUGCGGAGGCUUUUGGAUAUGGGGAGUGAUGGUGUCCUGUCUGUCUCCCCCCUCGGUGUCUGCCGUUGACAUAGGGGCCAGCCAGCCCUAGACGGGAUGACUUCCGUUCCUGAGGACAGACACAGAGGGACUCCUGCUCAGCCUCACUAAUUGUUUAGACACAUUCCUUCCUACCCUUCUCUAGUCUCAGGAGAUGGUAACUGGGUCGCAUUUCAGUCUCUGACUGAGGCCUCAGCCAUUUUUACGGAAGUUCUUUUCUGUCUGACCUUGCUUAUAAAGCAUCGACGAGAAAAUUACAGUCUUCAACCCUCUUCUGGAUUGACAAAUUGUGGCUGGGAAGUGGCGAUCUAGCUUUCAGCCCAGUAACCAGUCUUUCAUGCCUACUACUCCCAGCAUUCCCUCCUCUCCCCACGUGUCUGUCCACACAGUGAAGAGGCCUGACCAGCCGUGGUACCAGGACAGGACGUGUCCAGGGAACGCUGACACCUGUCCUCGCGCCUUCUCAGUGGCCAGCGUGAUGAAACCAGCACGUCUCCGUGGAUGUGAUUGGGAACCCAGGGGCAGUGCCAGGGGGAGGGCUCCCUCGAGGAGGCUGUUUCUAACAGAUUUCCCCACUCAAAGAUCAGAUCACCAGCAGAGGAGCAUCAGAAACUGGCUCCACUGUUGGGCUUUUCAGAGAUUUUGGUCCCUGCGGGUUGCCUAAAUAGAUUCUGGCCCACAGUUUACCUCGAAAGGCUGUUGAUGUUGUUCUGUUUCUCCUCUUUCACUUAGAGAUCAAUGUUGAUUUUGCGUACACCAUGACAUCAGCGUUAGGCAAUUAGGAGAAAAAAAUCUAAUCAUUUCGCCUUUAUUUCAAGUGGUUCUUGAAUUCCCUCCAGUCUCAUUGUGAAAGGGGCAGGGAAAAAAAUAAAAGGGUAAUAAUCUGAUUUCUGUCCAUAUUUCCAGUGUUUUAUGCUUUCCAUUAAAACCUUGCUAAUCUCUCGCGUGCUGUUCCUUUUUUGAACUGCAGGGUCAAAAAUGUUCCCCUCCCCCACUUCUGUUUCCUGAGUGGGCUGUCUUCAAAAAGUAUAAAUACUAUUGAUCGUGGUAUUUAAUACACUAAUGAAACCCAUGGUUAUUGACUACAUAAUUAAUAUACUGUCCAAAAGUGAAGUUUGGCCGCCCAGUAUGUAAAGGUUUAUAUUGACUCAUGUUUCUUUGGCAAUAUGCCGCCCAAGGUUUUAUUUAUAGAGGAUGAAACAGGUUGUUUGGUCUCCUUUUCUUCUUUUCACCUGUUAGAAGGCCACUAUUCCCCUAGUAAACUGAUUGUUUCCUUGUCUCAAAGGGAAGAUUCCCCCCACUCCCCGGCCACCUUUUAUGUGGUUUGUUAACUCUUAGUCUUAUAUCCACUCCGCUGGUAGAGUUCUGGCUUUUAUAAACACCUUUGGAAGUCAUCGGUUCCUCAAAAAGAGAGCAUAGAUGUUUAAUUUUCACUUAUUCAAAAAAACUGGUAUUUUUGUUAUUAAGACA